CCGCGCUGUCCGCCGCCGCUGCCUGAGUCGACUCUGCGCCGCCCGCCGCGAUGGAGGCCGCCGCCCAGUUCUUCGUCGAGAGCCCGGACGUGGUCUACGGCCCCGAGGCCAUCGAGGCGCAAUACGAGUACCGGACGACGCGCGUCAGCCGCGAGGGUGGCGUUCUCAAGGUGCACCCCACGUCCACGCGCUUCACCUUCCGGACCGCCCGGCAGGUGCCCCGGCUCGGGGUCAUGCUUGUCGGCUGGGGCGGGAACAACGGCUCCACACUCACCGCCGCGGUGCUGGCCAAUCGACUGCGUUUGUCCUGGCCCACGCGCAGCGGCCGCAAGGAGGCCAACUACUACGGCUCGCUGACUCAGGCGGGCACCGUGAGCCUGGGCCUGGACGCCGAGGGCCAGGAGGUGUUCGUACCCUUCAGCGCGGUGCUGCCCAUGGUGGCGCCCAACGACCUCGUGUUCGAUGGCUGGGACAUCUCGUCGCUGAACCUGGCCGAGGCGAUGCGGCGCGCGAAGGUGCUGGACUGGGGGCUGCAGGAGCAACUGUGGCCGCACAUGGAGGCCCUGCGGCCCCGGCCUUCUGUUUACAUCCCCGAAUUCAUCGCGGCCAACCAGAGCGCGCGCGCGGACAACCUCAUCCCAGGCUCGCGUGCGCAGCAGGUGCUGUCCCAUCCCGCAUCCCUUGCUUCCUGCCACCUGUUCUUCGCCACUUGGUUCCCUCUUUUUGCCCCACCCCGCGAAUCCAGGCCUCACUUGACACCCGGGGAACUGAGUAGCCCAGGCCUCUGUGAGUCCGAGAGUAUGUACAACCAACUUCCCUACACCCUCUCCAUCCUCCCCACACCCUCACCAUCCAACCCACAGCUGGAGCAGAUCCGCAGGGACAUCCGAGACUUCCGGUCUAGCGCGGGGCUGGACAAAGUCAUAGUGCUGUGGACGGCGAACACGGAGCGCUUCUGUGAGGUGAUUCCAGGCCUCAACGACACAGCCGAGAACCUGCUGCGCACCAUUGAGCUCGGUCUGGAGGUGUCGCCCUCCACGCUCUUCGCCGUGGCCAGCAUCCUGGAGGGCUGUGCCUUCCUCAAUGGGUCUCCGCAGAACACCCUGGUGCCCGGAGCUCUUGAGCUCGCGUGGCAGCACCGGGUUUUUGUGGGCGGAGAUGACUUCAAGUCAGGCCAGACCAAAGUCAAGUCCGUGCUUGUGGACUUCCUCAUUGGCUCCGGCCUCAAGACCAUGUCCAUCGUGAGUUACAACCACCUGGGCAACAACGAUGGGGAGAACCUAUCGGCGCCAUUGCAGUUCCGCUCUAAGGAGGUGUCCAAGAGCAACGUGGUGGACGACAUGGUGCAGAGCAACCCAGUGCUCUAUACGCCCGGCGAAGAGCCUGACCACUGCGUGGUCAUCAAGUAUGUGCCGUACGUGGGUGACAGCAAGCGCGCGCUGGAUGAGUAUACCUCGGAGCUGAUGCUGGGCGGAACCAACACACUGGUGCUGCACAACACGUGUGAGGACUCGCUGCUGGCCGCACCCAUCAUGCUGGACCUAGCGCUGCUGACCGAGCUGUGCCAGCGCGUGAGCUUCUGCACUGACAUGGACCCCGAGCCGCAGACCUUCCACCCCGUGCUGUCCCUGCUCAGCUUCCUCUUCAAGGCGCCACUAGUGCCGCCCGGCAGCCCGGUGGUCAAUGCGCUUUUCCGCCAGCGCAGCUGCAUCGAGAACAUCCUCAGGGCCUGCGUGGGGCUCCCGCCACAGAACCACAUGCUCCUGGAACACAAAAUGGAGCGCCCAGGGCCCAGCCUCAAGCGAGUUGGACCCGUGGCUGCCACCUACCCUAUGUUGAACAAGAAAGGACCGGUACCCGCUGCCACCAAUGGCUGCACCGGUGAUGCCAAUGGGCAUCUGCAAGAGGAGCCCCCAAUGCCCACCACCUGAGGCCCCGGUCACACAGUUUCUCGGCUCUUCCUCCCCGCUGCCCCCCACGACCCUACCUUGAAGGCCCCCACAAAUAAAGGCGCUGCCACUCAGCCCUCCUUCCACCUGGGGUUCUUGGGGCCUGUGACCUGACUCUGCCUCCCUCUACUUCCCCGACUCUUGAGCGCCCAGCUUCAGUCCCAUCCCCUCUGCCCAUGGUCAUCACCCCAACUCCCAGGGAGAGCCCAGAACCUGGAGCCUCGCUCUGCCCCCAGUUCUCAAAGGUGGGGCUAGAUGGGGGCGGGGACGGAACAAGACCACAGGGUGGAGAGUGUGGUGGCAGAAGGCCAAAGAGGGAAUCUGAGACAAGCUACCAAAAACCAAAACCAGCUUCCAUUUAUUUAUGGGCCCCACCCCCUGACGUCCUGGGGAGAGGGGCCCCCCAAAGAGCCUUUCUCUCUGGGACAAAAUACAAAUGGCAGGAAGGGUCCAUACAGAAAAGAACGUCUCUGAGGUCCUUGCGUUUUUAAUAAAAUGGUAAGAGUC